AGUGCGCAGCAGGGCAGGUUCCUGCGGAGCCGCCGGAGACGGUCGGGUUUGCCAGGGCCGGGCGGGACCGCGGGGACCAUGGCGGAGCCGCCUCGGCUACCUCUGACUUUUGAGGAUGUUGCUAUUUAUUUCUCCGAGCAAGAAUGGCAGGAUCUAGAGGCAUGGCAGAAGGAACUUUACAAGCAUGUGAUGAGAAGCAAUUAUGAGACUCUCGUCUCUCUAGAUGAUGGACUUCCAAAACCAGAACUAAUAUCCUGGAUUGAACACGGGGGAGAGCCCUUCAGGAAAUGGAGAGAAUCACAGAAAUCAGGAAACAUAAUUUGCUCCUCUGUUGAUAUGCAUUUUGAUCCAGGUUUUGAGGAACAGCUGUUUUGGGGAAGCCAGCAGGCUAUGAAUUCAGGAAAAACUAAAAGCCAUUUCCAAUUAGAUCCUGAAAGCCAGUGUUCCUUUGGAUCCUUUGUUUCCUUCAGGCCUGACCAAGGCAUCACCCUCGGGAGCCCACAGAGACACGACGCCAGGGCUCCUCCACCACUAGCCUGCGGCCCCAGUGAAUCUACCCUAAAAGAAGGAAUCCCAGGUCCCAGAAAUCUGGAUCUUCCUGGUUUGUGGGACGUCCCCGCCUGGGAGAGCACCCAGCACCCUUGGCCUGUCUGCGGGGAAAGCUGUUGGGAGAACAACCAUUUAGUAAUGCACCAGAGAGGCCACUCAAAGGACCGGACACGUAGGGCCUGGGAGAAAUUCAACAAGAGGGCGGAGACGCAGAUGCCGUGGAGCAGCCCUCGGGUACAGAGGCACUUCCGGUGUGGCGUGUGCGGUAAGAGCUUCCGCCGGAAGCUGUGUCUGCUGCGCCAUCUGGCGGCCCACACGGGGAGGGGCCCCUUCCGGAACGCUGACGGUGAAAUGUGCUUCCGACACGAGCUGACCCAUCCCAGCCACCGCCUCCCGCAGCAGGGGGAGAAGCCUGCCCAGUGCACCCCAUGCGGCAAGCGCUCCCUCCCAGUGGACAGCACGCAGGCUCGCCGGUGCCAGCACAGCCGGGAGGGGCCGGCCUCUUGGAGAGAAGGCCGCGGGGCCUCCAGCAGUGUGCACUCGGGACAGAAACCAGGCUCGCGCCUGCCCCAGGAGGGGAACAGCCACCAGGAAGGGGACACGGAGGCGCUGCAGCAUGGCGCAGAGGGGCCCUGCUCCUGCUCGGAGUGUGGCGAGCGCUCCCCUAUGAGCGCCAGGCUCGCCAGCCCCUGCAGGGCGCAUACUGGAGAAAAGCCCUUCCAGUGUGCGCAUUGCACCAAGCGCUUCCGCCUGCGCCGCCUGCUGCAGGUCCACCAGCACGCGCACGGUGGGGAGAGACCGUUCUCCUGCAGGAAGUGUGGCAAGGGCUUCGCCAAGCAGUGUAAACUCACGGAGCACAUUCGAGUCCACAGCGGAGAGAAGCCUUUCCGGUGUGCCAAGUGUGGCAGGAACUUCCGUCAGAGGGGACAGCUGCUGCGGCACCAGCGGCUGCACACGGACGAGAAGCCCUUUCAGUGCCCAGAGUGUGGGCUGAGCUUCCGCCUGGAGAGCAUGCUGAGAGCCCACCGGCUCCGGCACGGUGGGGAGAGGCCGUUCUCCUGUAGCGAGUGUGGCAGAGGCUUCACCCACCAGUGCAAGCUCCGUGAGCACCUGAGAGUGCACAGCGGGGAGAGGCCCUUCCAGUGCCUGAAGUGCGACAAGCGCUUCCGCCUGAAGGGCAUCCUGAAGGCCCACCAGCACACGCACAGCAAGGAGAGGCCGUUCUCGUGCGGGGAGUGUGGCAAGGGCUUCACCAGACAAUCCAAGCUCACGGAGCACUUGCGCGUGCACAGCGGGGAGAGACCCUUCCAGUGCCCAGAGUGCAACAGGAGCUUCCGCCUGAAGGGGCAGCUGCUCAGCCAUCAGCGCCUGCACACGGGAGAGAGGCCCUUCCAGUGUCCGGAGUGCGACAAGCGCUAUCGCGUGAAGGCCGACAUGAAGGCCCACCAGCUGCUGCACAGCGGGGAGAUGCCUUUCUCCUGUGAGUGCGGCAAGGGCUUUGUGAAACACUCAAAGCUCAUCGAGCACAUCAGAACGCACACGGGAGAGAAGCCUUUUCAGUGUCCCAAGUGUGACAAGAGUUUCCGCCUGAAGGCGCAGCUGCUCAGCCAUCAGGGCCUGCACACAGGGGAGAGGCCUUUUCACUGCCCUGAGUGUGACAAGAACUUCCGGGAAAGGGGACACAUGCUGAGGCACCAGCGCAUCCACAGGCCCGAGAGGCCCUUUGCCUGUGGCGAUUGUGGGAAGGGCUUCAUUUACAAGUCUAAGCUUGCGGAGCACAUCAGAGUACACACAAAAUCCUGUCCUGCUCCAAAUGAACUGGACAUUAAGAAAAGGCUCAGCCAACUGUUUGCAAUGAUAGAGGCCGAUUGGAGUUGAGGCAGAGUGGGACAUCCAAAGCGUUGAGCAGGAUUGGUAUUGCCCAGGAAUCCACAGCAACAGUAGCCAGACCCGCUGGUAGACGGGUUUUAGGAGCAGGUAUCCUUCUUUGAGCAAGAGUGUCAUGCAAGUUAGGAAUAUGAAGAACCACAAAGGAUUUUCUCUUCAGAAGCAUCACCAAUUAUAUUUCUUUCUUUUUUUUUUUUUUUUCCAAGAUGGAGUUUUGCUCUGUCACCCAGGCUGGAGUGCAGUGGCGUGAUCCCAGCUAUAUUGGAAAAGACAGCAUUAUAAAACAAGGACAUAAUUUUAUGAAAAAGGAGGCAUCUGCAAACGAAAACAAUUUCUACGAGGUUAUAUGUGAUUGUUAACAUUUUUAAGAAAAGGUGCACACAGAAAUCCAGAUAAGAUGUGAUUACCUUUGUGCAUUUGUAUAAAAAUAUAUGUGUGUAAUUAUAAGGAAGUUCUGACAUUUUAAAAAGUAAUUGUUAUAAAAGUAAAUUUAGGCCAGGCACAGUGGUUCAUGCCUGUAAUCCCAGCACUUGGGAGGCCGUGGCAGGAGGAUCACGAGCCAAGGAGUUUGAGACCAGCUUGGGCAACAUGGCAAAACCCUGUCUCUACUAAAAAUACAAAAAUUAGCCAGGCAUGGUGGUACACACCAGUAGUCCCAGCUACUCCUGAAGCUGAGGUGGGAGGAUCGCCUGAGCCCAGGGAGGUCAAGGCUGCAGUGAGCAAUGAUGGUGCCACUGCACUCCAGUAUGGAUGACAUAGUAUGACACUGUCUC